AAGCACCGCGCAGCCGCCUCCGCCGCAGGAUCCCCCGGUGCAGGCCUCCGUGCUGGUGCGGAUCCUGGAGCUCAGCCGCGCGCGCCCUGCCCGAUCCUGUGCCGACCCACCGCACUAUGCGCGCCGUGCCGCUGCCCGCCCCGCUCCUGCCGCUGCUGCUGCUCGCGCUCCUGGCCGCUCCCGCCGCCCGCGCCAGCAGAGCCGAGUCCGUCUCCGCGCCGUGGCCCGAACCCGAGCGCGAGUCGCGGCCACCGCCCGGCCCGGGGCCCGGGAACACCACCCGGUUUGGGUCUGGGGCGGCGGGCGGCAGCGGCAGCUCCAGCUCCAACAGCAGUGGCGACGCCUUGGUGACCCGCAUUUCCAUCCUCCUCCGCGACCUACCCACCCUCAAGGCAGCCGUGAUCGUGGCGUUCGCCUUUACCACCCUCCUCAUCGCCUGCCUGCUGCUGCGCGUCUUCAGGUCGGGAAAGAGGUUAAAGAAGACACGCAAGUAUGAUAUCAUCACCACUCCAGCAGAGCGAGUGGAAAUGGCGCCACUAAAUGAAGAGGAUGAUGAAGAUGAGGACUCCACAGUAUUCGACAUCAAAUACAGGUAAAACCUGUUUCCCAGCCUGGUGGCAUCCUGUGGAAAGUUGGUCAGCUGCAACCUGGGGUGUGAAGGACUGGACCUGGAAGCCCUCUUGCGUCGGAGGUGUUGAAACCAAAACGAACGUUAUGUAUAAAACCCCAGCUCCAUCGUGCGUGUCAGGCAUCUGCUCAGACUGUCACUGGCAAGCUCGUUUCCACGUCACCACAAUGGAGUUGCUUCUGCCACCCUUUGGGCAUCCCUUUAAAGUGCCCCCUACUUCUACUCCCCAUGUAAGAGGCUUUGUGCCUUGCUAAGGAGCAAAGGGUAGAAACAUGUUGAUUUUAAAGAAGUUUUUUUAAGACAAUUGUUGACAAUAGUAAAAGAGAUCAGGAGGAUCAAGAAUCUAAAACAAGCCUGAAGGAUGUCCAACUGUGUAUUUAGAAUUUCCGACAUUCUUCUCUACUGGAUCUACACAUUGGACCCCAUCUGAUCCUUUGCUGCUUUUUUGGCUUGGUCAGGUCCUGGCCUCAUUUUGGCGUUACCUGUGUCAGAGUUCAAGGUGGAUGUGCUUAGAGCUGGUCAGCCCCUUCCAGACCUGGACACGUCUGUGGCUCCUUUUCUUUCUUCCUUUUUUUUUUUUUUUAAAAAAAAAAAAGGUUCAGCAGAAAUCAGCGUGGCUAGUUCACAAAGAAUUUCCAGUAUCAGGGAAAAACUGUGCGUGUGUGUGUGUGUGUGUGUGCACGUGUGUGCGUGUGCACGUGUGUGAUACCUAUAAAACAGUUUCUCCUUCUCUGAAGGGAAAGGAAAGUGCUAGGCAGCCUGUGAUUAGCAACAUUCUUUGUGCUUUUUUGUUGUUCCUCUGCUCUGUCACAGUUCUACGUUGUUUGCCUUAGAAAUGUAAUUUUUAAAAACCAUUUUAAAAAUGAACGGUGAUUUGGCUGGCUGGAAAAAAUCACACUGUCAGGGGACUAUAUUUGAAGUCAGUCUAGACGGGGCUGGACUAGGAACCCACCUGGACCCAGGAGACCCCACAGGACCCAGGAGGUCCCUGCCGGAAGGCAGAGGUUCAGGUGAGAGUGGCUCACCUCUGAGCUGGUGAAGUGAGGACUUGCCUGUGACAUGACCCAGGGAUCUGCUGCUGGCUUCUGGAGACAGGGCCUUGGGCUGACUUCUCAGGUUGAUUGAGGCCUCCUGACUAGCGGUGUUCCCAGGCUAGAGGUGAUUGGCUGCAACAAAGAUGCUUCUAUUAGUCUAUUAGCAGUGCCUUCGGGACCCUGGGAUUUUGCUCUCUCUAGAAAGGUGUUUUUUAUUUUUUUAUUUUUUAUCUCCCCCUUUUUUCCUGGCUUUGCUCCAGGGUUUGUGUAUUUGCCUGUUUAUUGUCCUGCUCUUUUUUUUUUUGGAUGAAAACUCCAGCCUUUCCUGACUCACCUCCAUCUUCGGUUCUUCAGUUUUCUGAGAAGAGUUGGGAUAUGUGGGAAGGGGCAUGGGAGCUCGGCAGCCUCCGCCUGCCAGGAAGGCAGUUUCGCCUCUGCAGGAAAGAGCAGAGCCCGUGGGAAGCCCUGGGUGAGGGUGGCGCAGCCGGCCCAGCACGCAUGGUAUUGCCAGCCACGGGGGGCCUGCGUGUAGUCUCUGCUCCCUGCAUUUCACCUUCUUUGUUGACUUUCCUUCUCUGUUUUCCCCCAUCUGUUUGCCAGAGGGGUGGGACUGGCAACAGAACAGCCGUGGCUGCUUUAUCUCUCCUCUCCACGGUGUACUCAGGCCUGAGUGGUGACUCACGGGAGCCUGGCCACCUCGCAGCUGUUCGCCCCCUCAACCUUUGAACUGGAACUGCUGGCUCACACAGGGUUUUCGACAACUGCAGCUGAAUCUCAUGGAAAAGCUGGAUUCCUCUGCCUUACGCAGAAACACCCGGGCUCCAUCUGCCAGGUGCUUGCCACUGGUCCUGGCAGAAAUGGCGGCUGCUGAAAGUGACCUUCCAAAUCCUUGGUGGCACUUCAGCGCCACAGGCUCUCCAAUAAAAACCCUUUACACACAAA